GUUGCCGGGCAACGCGCUGUCCAUGUCGCGGGCCUCGCUGGGACUCCCUGGGAGAUGAGGCCGCGAGGUCUCCCGCCGCUCCUGGUGGUGCUCCUGGGCUGCUGGGCCUCCGUGAGCGCCCAGACCGAUGCCACCCCGGCGGUGACGACAGAGGGCCUCAACUCCACCGAGGCAGCCCUGGCCACCUUCGGAACUUUCCCGUCGACCAGGCCCCCCGGGACUCCCAGGGCUCCAGGGCCCUCCUCCGGCCCCAGGCCUACCCCAGUCACGGACGUUGCUGUUCUCUGUGUCUGUGACUUAUCCCCAGCACAGUGUGACAUCAACUGCUGCUGUGAUCCCGACUGCAGCUCCGUGGAUUUCAGUGUCUUUUCUGCCUGCUCAGUUCCAGUUGUCACGGGCGACAGCCAGUUUUGUAGUCAAAAAGCAGUCAUCUAUUCAUUGAAUUUUACAGCAAACCCACCUCAAAGAGUAUUUGAACUUGUUGACCAGAUUAAUCCAUCUAUUUUCUGCAUUCAUAUUACAAACUCACAUUUUACUCCAGGACUUUCACGGUGGCUGUGUGAGAGUAGAAGUCGGAUUCUUUCAUUCCCAUAGCCAUCCGGAGAGAGCUUCUCCUUACAGGUUGAUACAGCAAACUCAUCAGUCCAGGGGCUAGAGAAAUAGACGGAUUAUUAUUGGCUUCUGUUGUGCUGUUUACUUAUAAACCUGCAUUAUCCUUUAUUAAUCCAGAAGUACCUGAUGAAAACAAUUUUGAUACAUUGAUGAAAACAUCUGAUGGUUUUACAUUGAAUGCUGAAUCAUAUGUUUCCUUCACAACCAAACUGGAUAUUCCUACUGCUGCUAAAUAUGAGUAUGGGGUUCCUCUGCAGACUUCAGAUUCGUUUCUGAGAUUUCCUUCGUCCCUGACAUCAUCUCUGUGCACUGAUAAUAACCCUGCAGCGUUUCUGGUGAACCAGGCUGUUAAGUGCACCAGAAAAAUAAAUUUAGAACAGUGUGAAGAAAUUGAAGCCCUCAGCAUGGCUUUUUACAGCAGCCCGGAAAUUCUGAGGGUACCUGAUUCAAGAAAAAAGGUCCCUAUCACUGUUCAGUCCAUCGUCAUUCAGUCUCUAAAUAAAACGCUCACCCGACGGGAGGACACUGAUGUGCUGCAGCCGACUCUCGUCAACGCUGGACACUUUAGCCUUUGCGUGAAUGUUGUUCUUGAGGUAAAGUACAGCCUCACAUACACAGAUGCAGGUGAAGUCACCAAAGCUGAUCUCUCAUUCGUUCUGGGGACAGUUAGCAGCGUAGUGGUCCCACUGCAGCAAAAGUUUGAAAUUCAUUUUCUUCAGGAAAAUACCCAGCCAGUCCCUCUCAGUGGAAACCCUGGUUAUGUCGUGGGGCUCCCAUUAGCUGCUGGAUUCCAGCCUCAUAAGGGGUCUGGGAUUAUUCAGACCACAAAUAGAUAUGGACAGCUUACUAUUCUUCAUAGCACAACUGAGCAAGACUGCUUAGCACUGGAGGGGGUCCGGACCCCAGUAUUAUUUGGUUACACUAUGCAAUCUGGCUGUAAACUAAGACUGACUGGAGCUCUCCCGUGUCAGCUCGUAGCACAGAAGGUGAAGAGCCUGCUGUGGGGCCAGGGCUUCCCAGAUUACGUGGCCCCUUUUGGAAAUUCCCAGGCCCAGGACAUGCUGGACUGGGUGCCCAUCCACUUCAUCACCCAGUCAUUCAACAGGAAGGAUUCCUGCCAGCUCCCAGGGGCUUUGGUUAUAGAAGUGAAGUGGACUAAAUACGGAUCCCUGCUGAAUCCACAGGCCAAAAUAGUCAAUGUAACUGCAAAUCUAAUUUCAUCCUCCUUUCCUGAGGCCAACUCAGGAAAUGAAAGGACGAUUCUUAUUUCCACUGCGGUUACUUUUGUGGAUGUGUCUGCACCUGCAGAGGCAGGCUUCAGAGCUCCACCAGCCAUCAAUGCCAGGCUGCCCUUUAACUUCUUCUUCCCGUUUGUUUGACAAUGCUCAGAUGCAUCAGUUCCUUAAUAUACACGUGAAAUUUGAAAACUGUACAUUCGGUGAGAUUAAAUUUUAUAUACAACUAGCAAUUGUCCAGCUUUGUUGCUCAUUUUCAAUUAAGGCUAAAGUGUUCAACAUGAGAAAAUGUGAUACAUUUGAUACAGUGUGGGGUGGGAGUGGAUGGGCAGCUCUUGGUGGUACUGGACCUUCCACAAGGCUGUGUCCACCCAGAAUCCAUGCUGGCAGGAGGGAGGCAGAGGUAUCAAACCAAACCUCUCACCAAGCGGCCCAGGAGGGGCAGCUGUUCCUCUCGUGACAGCACAGGCCCAUGAGACAGUGUCUUCUUUUUGAGGGGAGCUGGUCCGGGUCUAGUUCACUUCACCAAGAAG